GAUGCAGCAGAAGCCUCCAGGCCAGAACUACCCAGUCUUGGACCUAUGGUGGAGAUAGAGCAUAGCUGGCGAUCAUGUGUACUUACACUCUAAGGUCACCUGGUUGCACUAUGGCCUCAUCUGUGGCUCUGAAAAUGAAGAUUUGGAAGGAGAUCAUCACAGCUAAUGUUAACAAGCCCCUCCUGUGUGCCAAAUCAUUCACCCCUCACCACAACCGAAUGAGCUAAGGAUUCUCGUUAUAUAUAGUUUAUGGAGAGGGAAGUGCAGACAUAAAGAGGUGAAUUAUCUUACCCAGAUCACACAGCUGAUAAGUGGUGGAGGCAGAAUAGAAUCUAAACAGUGUGGCUCCGGAGCCCACAUGCAUUGAUUCGACAAGUGUUUAUUGAGCACCUGCCGCGGACAAGGCCUUGUGUGAUUAAACAGGGUUAUAAUUAGUAAUGUAAAAAUGAGAAAUCACUAAUGCUUUUUAGACUUAACAUUUUCUUUUUUUGUAGGUUUCAGGCACAGAACUGUAUAUCCAAUAAUAGUGAAAUGGAUCCCACUAAUUAUGACCGAAAUGAUGAUACAUUUAAAUGACUUGGAUGUUUUAUAGGUAUGAUCUCGUGAAACCUUGAGAGAAACUGAAUGACGAAUGAAACUAUUGUUCCUGUUUCACACAGAAGAAAACUGAGGUUAAAAGGGGUUGGCACUCAUCAUGAGCCCCUGUUCUCAUUCUGCAAAUGGUGAAGCUCUCUAUUGUCCUGACCCCACGGUUCCUGUCCCAUGACCAGGGCCAGCUCACCAAGGAGCUGCAGCAGCACGUAAAGUCAGUGACAUGCCCAUGCGAGUACCUGAGGAAGGUGACCUUGAGGAACCCUGGGAGCUCAGGAAGGAAGGAGCGCCCAGAAGCAGGGACAGGGAGCUGGUUGGGGAGGACCAGAAAUCAGGUUAUCAAUACUCUGGCUGACCAUCGUCAUCGUGGGACUGACUUUGGUGGAAGUCCUUGGUUACUUAUCAUUACUGUGUUUCUGAGAAGUUAUAAAUUUGCCAUCUCCCUCUGCACAAGUUACCUUUGUGUGUCUUUCCUGAAGACUAUCUUCCCGUCUCAAAAUGGACAUGAUGGAUCCACGGAUGUACAGCAGAGAGCCAGGAGGUCCAACUGCCGUAGACAGGAAGGAAUUAAAAUUGUCCUGGAAGACAUCUUUACUUUAUGGAGACAGGUGGAAACCAAAGUUCGAGCUAAAAUCCGUAAGAUGAAGGUGACAACAAAAGUCAACUGUCAUGACAAAAUCAAUGGAAAGAGGAAGACCGCCAAAGAACAUCUGAGGAAACUAAGCAUGAAAGAACGUGAGCACGGAGAAAAGGAGAGGCAGGUGUCAGAGGCAGAGGAAAAUGGGAAAUUGGAUAUGAAAGAAAUACACACCUACAUGGAAAUGUUUCAACGUGCGCGAGCGUUGCGGCGGCGGGCAGAGGACUACUACAGAUGCAAAAUCACCCCUUCUGCAAGAAAGCCUCUUUGCAACCGGGUAAGUUUGCUUGUUUUCCUUGCUUUUGGACAUAGUCUGCCAGGUCAGGACAUGGAUACAUUUUUCUCCCUACGGCUCUGUGCUCAAGCCCUGCAGAGGGAGAUGGCAGAGAGGAAGGCUGCCUACAAGCAUCACAGUCCCAUCCCUGUUGGUAACCGUGUUGCGCAAAAACACCUUCAUCCCCACCCAGUGGGGCCCCCAUCUAAUAUUCUAAGUGUCAGAGGUUCCAUAUUUGUAAUAGCAAAUGGGCCCUGACUGUAAAUUAGUGAAGAGUGAAUGUAACUUAUUACCCACAGGGACAAUUCCAAAUGAAGGCCUUAAAUGAUGCUCAGCUAAGCUGGUUCUUGUGUGGCCUCUGUACCUUCAAAAGCUGCCGAGUCCUAUGAUUACACGCGAUGGGACUUGUACACUUGAAGUGAAACACAGUUUUAAAACUUGCUUUGUUUAGAAUUCCCACCUCAUUUUUCCAUGGACAAAAGUAUUCUUUAGGUCCUAGUGCACUUACAAUUUGGUAUUACCUGGGAGUGAAAAGAAAUAUUACAGCCAUGCCUAACUGACUUCUUGAGGUAAGAUUGUUCUGUCAGAAAACCCUCUCCCAGUUCCCCUGCAGCUCUUCAGGAAUCCACAUCUCUCCAGAGCUCUUUGUUCUCAUGGGUGGCACCUCCAGAGUGAAGAAGAUCCUUUGUCAAGAAGGGAAACAGAGGGGAAAUGAGAGGGUCCUGCAGGCAGAGCUGGAAUCAACUUCCACUCUGCCUCUUGCAAGCUGUGUGACCCUGGGCACAAUUUCUCCUUCCUCUGGAAACCUCUGUUUUCUUAGAUUUGGAGCAGGGUGGUCACACUGACCUUGCAGAGUUCUGAGAAUCAGAGACAGAACAUAAAAGGCCUGGAAAACAUUCUCCAAAAAGAAGCUGCAACAUGUGUGGACAAUGGGCUUUUCAUGCCUCUCUUACUGUCUCUUACUGUCUAUUGACCUGGUGCAAGAAACAUGCUCUGGUGAUGGCUGUGAGGGAGGAAUGAGGAUAGACAUAGACACUCCUGUGUCUCAAACAUGCUUCUUUAUUACUCUGUUAUGACUCUGUCUUCCCUGGGGCAGGACCCCAGCCUGCCUACAUUUGCAGACAGACACAGUGGCAUGUGGAGACAACAGUGUGUCCCAAUGACUUUUCUUUACCCCCCAGCUGUCGGCAGUACUCAGUGGAAGGGUGAUAUUAUGACACUGACACUGCUAUUUUGAAACCUGGAGGAUGGAAAGGUGCAAAAAUCUAUCACCAGCAACAGAAGGUGCAGACUGUGUUGGUGGCGGUAAUUUUGUCCAUCAAAUGAAUAUGUGUGAAAACAUUCCCUCCUUUGGCCCUACAGGUCAGAAUGGCGGCAGUGGAGCAUCGUCAUUCUUCAGGAUUGCCCUACUGGCCCUACCUCACAGCUGAAACUUUAAAAAACAGGAUGGGCCACCAGCCACCUCCUCCAACUCAACAACAUUCUAUAAUUGAUAACUCCCUGAGCCUCAAGACACCUUCCGAGCGUCUGCUCUAUCC